AGUGCAGGUGCCGCUGCGCCGGGGCCGGGGAGGCGCGCGCCGAGCCGAGCGGAGCCUAGGAGGGAUGGAGAGCUGGCCACCCGGGCUGCAGGAGCACCGGCGCGGGGCGUAGGCGGCGCGAGGCGGGCGCGAGGCGGGCGCUCGGGCGCGAGGCGCGUGCGGGCGCGGGAGCACUUUGCGAUAGGAUGAGGCUCCGGGCUGGCGCGGUAGUACUAUGAUUUGGUAUGUGGCCACUUUCAUAGCAAGUGUGAUCGGCACCCGAGGGCUUGCGGCUGAAGGCGCCCACGGCCUGCGAGAGGAGCCCGAGUUUGUGACGGCAAGAGCUGGGGAGAGCGUGGUCCUGCGAUGCGACGUGAUCCACCCAGUGACGGGACAGCCCCCACCCUAUGUCGUAGAGUGGUUCAAGUUCGGGGUCCCCAUCCCUAUCUUCAUCAAGUUUGGCUACUACCCGCCGCACGUGGACCCUGAGUAUGCAGGCCGGGCCAGUCUUCAUGAUAAGGCAUCUCUGCGGCUGGAACAAGUUCGCUCUGAGGACCAGGGCUGGUAUGAGUGCAAAGUGCUCAUGCUGGACCAGCAGUAUGACACCUUCCACAAUGGCAGCUGGGUCCACCUCACCAUCAACGCCCCUCCCACCUUUACAGAAACACCCCCCCAGUACAUCGAGGCCAAGGAGGGUGGUAGUAUCACCAUGACCUGCACAGCUUUUGGGAACCCCAAGCCCAUUGUCACCUGGCUCAAGGAGGGGACGCUCCUCGGUGCUAGUGGGAAAUACCAGGUGAGUGACGGCAGCCUGACAGUGACAUCGGUCAGUCGGGAGGACAGAGGUGCCUACACCUGCCGAGCGUACAGCAUUCAGGGGGAGGCUGUCCACACGACUCACCUGCUUGUCCAAGGGCCCCCUUUCAUCGUCUCCCCUCCUGAGAACAUCACCGUCAACAUCUCCCAGGAUGCUCUGCUCACCUGCCGGGCAGAGGCGUAUCCGGGCAACCUCACCUACACCUGGUACUGGCAGGACGAGAACGUCUACUUUCAGAACGACCUGAAGCUGAGGGUGCGCAUCCUAAUCGAUGGGACCCUGAUCAUCUUCCGGGUGAAGCCGGAGGACUCGGGGAAGUACACCUGUGUGCCCAGCAACAGCCUGGGGCGCUCCCCCUCCGCCUCGGCGUACCUGACCGUGCAGUACCCAGCGCGUGUCCUCAACAUGCCCCCUGUGAUUUACGUGCCCGUGGGGAUCCAUGGCUACAUCCGCUGCCCUGUGGACGCAGAACCACCGGCCACCGUGGUCAAGUGGAACAAGGACGGCCGUCCCCUGCAGGUUGAGAAGAACCUCGGUUGGACCCUGAUGGAGGAUGGCUCCAUUCGAAUUGAGGAGGCCACAGAGGAGGCUCUUGGCACUUAUACCUGUGUGCCUUACAACACUCUGGGGACCAUGGGCCAGUCUGCCCCUGCGAGGCUUGUCCUGAAGGACCCCCCCUAUUUCACGGUGCUACCAGGCUGGGAGUACAGGCAGGAGGCCGGCCGGGAGCUACUUAUCCCCUGUGCUGCCGCAGGGGACCCCUUUCCUGUCAUCACUUGGAGAAAGGUAGGGAAGCCCAGCAGAAGCAAGCACAGUGCCCUGCCCAGUGGGAGCCUGCAGUUCCGUGCCCUGAGUAAGGAGGACCACGGGGAGUGGGAAUGUGUCGCCACCAACGUGGUCACGAGCAUCACUGCCAGCACCCACCUCACCGUCAUCGGCACCAGCCCCCAUGCCCCGGGCAGUGUCCGGGUCCAGGUCUCCAUGACAACUGCCAACGUGUCCUGGGAACCAGGCUAUGAUGGAGGCUACGAGCAGACAUUCUCAGUUUGGAUGAAGCGGGCACAGUUUGGGCCCCAUGACUGGCUGUCCUUGCCAGUGCCGCCAGGACCCAGCUGGCUGCUGGUGGACACCCUGGAGCCUGAGACAGCGUACCAGUUCAGCGUCCUGGCCCAGAACAAGCUGGGAACCAGCGCCUUCAGUGAGGUGGUCACUGUGAACACUUUAGCAUUCCCUAUUACAACUCCAGAACCCCUGGUGCUGGUCACCCCACCGAGGUGCCUCAUAGCCAAUCGGACUCAGCAGGGUGUGCUCCUGUCCUGGCUUCCGCCUGCCAACCACAGCUUUCCCAUCGACCGCUACAUCAUGGAGUUCCGUGUCGCAGAGCGCUGGGAGUUGCUCGACGAUGGCAUCCCCGGCACCGAAGGAGAGUUCUUUGCCAAGGAUCUGUCACAGGACACGUGGUAUGAGUUCCGGGUUCUGGCCGUCAUGCAGGAUCUGAUCAGCGAGCCCAGCAACAUCGCCGGCGUCUCCAGCACAGACAUCUUCCCGCAGCCGGACCUGACCGAGGAUGGGCUGGCGCGGCCUGUGCUGGCGGGAAUCGUAGCUACCAUCUGCUUCUUGGCAGCUGCCAUCCUGUUCAGCACCCUGGCUGCCUGCUUUGUCAACAAGCAGCGCAAGCGUAAGCUCAAGCGCAAAAAAGACCCUCCACUCUCCAUCACCCACUGCAGGAAGAGCCUGGAGUCUCCCUUGUCCUCUGGCAAGGUGAGCCCCGAGAGCAUCCGCACGCUCCGAGCGCCGUCAGAAUCCUCCGACGACCAGGGCCAGCCCGCGGCCAAGAGGAUGCUGAGCCCCACCCGUGAGAAGGAGCUGUCGCUGUACAAGAAGACCAAGCGGGCCAUCAGCAGCAAGAAGUACAGCGUGGCCAAGGCAGAGGCCGAGGCAGAGGCCACCACGCCCAUCGAGCUCAUCAGCAGAGGCCCUGACGGCCGCUUCGUGAUGGACCCUGCCGAGAUGGAGCCCUCGCUGAAGAGCAGGCGCAUCGAGGGCUUCCCCUUCGCCGAGGAGACGGACAUGUACCCCGAGUUCCGCCAGUCGGACGAGGAGAACGAGGACCCACUGGUGCCCACAUCUGUGGCCGCCCUGAAGUCCCAGCUCACCCCUCUGUCAUCCAGCCAGGAGUCCUACCUGCCACCACCAGCAUACAGCCCUCGGUUCCAGCCCCGCGGGCUGGAGGGCCCCGGUGGCCUGGAAGGUCGGCUUCAGGCCACAGGCCAGGCCCGGCCCCCUGCCCCCCGGCCCUUCCACCAUGGCCAGUAUUAUGGGUACCUCAGCAGCAGCAGCCCUGGGGAGGUGGAGCCGCCCCCGUUCUACGUGCCAGAAGUGGGCAGCCCCCUGAGCUCCGUCAUGUCGUCCCCGCCCCUGCCCACCGAGGGGCCCUUUGGCCACCCCACCAUCCCCGAGGAGAAUGGAGAGAAUGCAUCCAACAGCACGCUGCCCUUGACUCAGACACCUACAGGAGGGCGCUCCCCUGAGCCCUGGGGCCGGCCAGAAUUCCCCUUCGGGGGGCUGGAGACCCCAGCGAUGAUGUUCCCCCACCAGCUGCCACCCUGUGAUGUGCCCGAGAGUCUGCAGCCCAAGGCCGGCCUCCCCCGAGGACUGCCCCCCACCUCCCUGCAGGUGCCCGCGGCCUACCCGGGCAUCCUGUCUCUGGAGGCACCGAAGGGUUGGGCAGGCAAGUCGCCCGGCAGGGGCCCUGUCCCAGCGCCCCCCGCCGCCAAGUGGCAGGACAGACCUAUGCAACCUCUGGUAAGCCAAGGGCAGCUGCGACAUACAAGCCAAGGCAUGGGCAUACCUGUGCUGCCUUACCCCGAGCCGGCUGAGCCGGGGGCGCACGGCGGCCCCAGCACAUUUGGCCUGGACACCCGGUGGUAUGAGCCCCAGCCCCGGCCCCGGCCUAGCCCUCGGCAGGCCAGGCGCGCCGAGCCCAGUUUACAUCAAGUGGUGCUACAGCCCUCCCGGCUCUCACCUCUGACCCAAAGCCCCCUCAGCUCCCGCACCGGCUCCCCUGAGCUCGCCGCCCGUGCCCGGCCUCGCCCGGGCCUCCUGCAGCAGGCAGAGAUGUCAGAGAUCACCCUGCAGCCGCCGGCUGCAGUCAGCUUUUCUCGAAAGUCUACGCCGUCCACAGGCUCCCCCUCCCAGAGCAGCCGCAGUGGGAGUCCCAGCUACCGGCCCGCCAUGGGCUUCACCACUCUGGCCACCGGCUACCCUUCCCCUCCACCCGGCCCCGCCCCUGCUGGGCCUGGGGACAGCUUGGACGUGUUUGGACAGACGCCUUCCCCUCGAAGGACGGGGGAGGAAUUGCUCCGACCGGAGACCCCACCACCCACGUUACCUACUUCAGGAACACUUCCACCUGCACCCGGGAACGCUGCUGCGCCUGAGAGGCUGGAGGCUCUGAAAUACCAACGGAUAAAGAAGCCCAAAAAGUCAUCCAAGGGCUCUUCGAAGUCAAAGAAACGAUCCGACGAUUCUGCCUCCCAGACUCAGCAGCUUCCCAACUCUCAGGUUCUGUGGCCCGAUGAAGCUGUCUGCCUCCGAAAGAAGAAGAGACAUUCUCGUCCUGACCCCUUUGCCCGGCUCUCAGACUUGUGCCACCGCCAGCUUCCGGAAGACCAGACAGCGAUUCUCAACAGUGUGGACCACGAUGACCCAGGACAUGCCACUUUGCUGUGACUCCACCCCACUCUAGGUGUCCCCGGGGCGAGGUUGCUGGGCUCAGGCAGGGAGGGCCACUGUGUGGGGGUGUGUCCUCCUCCGUCUGCCAAGGGCGGCCCAGACCUUUGUCCUGCAUGCCCCCUCUUUUGCCAGAGCGGGUGUCUCCCUCCAGAUCCUGGCCGCCUGUCUUCAGGACGGAGGGUGGGCACACCUUCCACCUGUGGGUCGAGGUCAGGAAGUGGAUUGGAGACUGGGCAACACCUGUCUCCUCCCCUCCGCCCCCUGCUUCACUAGGUUGAUUUUUCUCAUCUCUUCCAAUGUCUUUGGAAGUGAAGAGGAAAGCAAUGGCUUUUACUGCUCUCUGCUUCUGUUUCAGUUUUUCAAGUCCUGGAAGAAGGCUGGACUUAAUGUCCAUCUUCCACACCCCACAUAUAUAUAGAUAUAGAUACAGAUGCAUAUGUCUGUAGUGUGUGGGUUUCUCUAUGUGUGUAUAUAUAUAUAUAUAUAUGUACAUUGAGGCAAAGUGCUGUUGCUCUCUGUGGUCAGUGGAGGCAGGAGGAGGAGGGCAGUGGCCAGCUGGGGUUUGCGAGCAGGGCUGGCUGCACGUUGGCCAGGUGCCUGACAUCUGUCUUGGGGGAUUCUUUCUCCCAAAACAAGAUCCGUGUCUCUCAGCUGAAUUCUCCGUGUGUCUCCUACCUUCUCCCACCCAGAGCAGAAAUGGGGCCUUGCUGUGAUUACCGGCUGCCUUCUAUGGGGGUUCAGUAAUGAGUUACUGCAGAACUAAAUUCAAGCCUUUGUUUCUUGGUUCCUGGGUGAAGAAGGGGUGGCCAGGCUCCUAGACCUGCAUCUUUCUUCCUUCCAGCGUGGCUCACGCUGCAGGAGUAGAGGCUAACUCAGCCGCGGGGCUAAAGCAAGCCUCUGGUGCACAUGUCCAGCGCAUCCGUCGGCGCCCUUCCGCCCAGCCAGGCCGUGAGCUCUGUGGCCAAAGUCUCCCCACUGCGGAGCCACCUGUGCUAGCGCCAAGCUGCCGGCUCUAUUUAUACCGUCCCCGGCUCAGCACUCUGUGCAGUGCUGUUCCACAGCGGCUGAUUGGAUCCUCCUUUGCUUUUGUGGGAGCUAAUUCUCCAGAUUGAUUAAUUACCACUUGUGCGGAGCCGCCUGUGGCUUUCCCGCACUCACCACGUGCUGCCUGCCGACUCUUCUCUGCCCCGGGGCCUUCGUCCUCCGGUGGACCUGAGCUGCAGGGGGAUGAGCUCAGGUGAAGCUAGGGCGCCUCUGGCUGCUGGGGCCUGGGACGCUCUGGAUCCUGCCCUCUUUGCCCAGUUCUAUUCUGUGGCUGAGGCGUAGGAAUGAAGGCGGGAGGGGUGGUGAGUAGGGUCUGGGCACUGACUCUUCCUCUGCCAAAGUCUGGUCCUGGUUCAAACUCGUAGCAUCCAGAAGCUUCCUGAGAUCAUCUUCCCACUAAGAUGUCUCUCUGCCGGUAAGAUAUGGUGCUGCCCAAGGGCAGGGCAGAAGGCCCCGAGGGCGGGGUGGAGGGGAGAUCUGCCCCUCCCCCACUCUUGUGUAGGAGCCCCCCUUCUGGCUUGGCUUAGAAUGAAGGUUCCUUGAAGUAUUUCCUUCUUGGUGCUGCUGUCUUGGUGGGUUUGGGGGCACCCACCUCUCCCGAGUUCCCUGCUUGGACGUGAGCCACGGCAGCAUUGGAUGGCUUCUGCUGGUCUCAUGCAGCUGCCAUGGGCUUGGCCCAGUGACCUCGCAGGAUGAGGCCUUGGAUGGCUGCUGUCUCUUCUUGGCGUUUCCAUCUUAGGGGAUGGACUUCUUCUGUGCCACACCGGCCCUGGUCCUUCCUUUCACCCAGGGAGCUGAGGACCAGCUCCACCCUUGAGGUUUACCGUGCAAGUAACACCACCGCAGUUCCUUUCUGAACACAUCUGAAGGGGUCAUGGUGAGAGAGGCACGCAGGGGCUUCUGAGACUGGGCCGUGCACCCUUGGGGUGGAACCUGGGCCUUCCAGUUGAUGUGCUUCUCUGGGGCGUUGGAAUCCACUUGACCACUGGGCACCAGCUCUGCGAGAUGGAAGAGCACACAACUCUUUGUGUUCUUUUUUCCAGGUAGCACACCCUCUGCCCCCGCGUCGUGAUGUGCUGCUCACUUGGGCGUCUCUCCUGGGGGAUGACGGGAGCCGGCUUACCUGAGGUGUUGGGGUGGGAGGUGGGGGCUUACCGCAAGCUGACGUGCAGCCUUUAUGCACUGGCAGUGUGAGAUUUCUACCCCAGAGGAGCUCACGGGGCUCAGCCAGGCCCUGGGAUGCACUGGGAUGUGGGCAUCAGGCUGUCAGCCUUCAGGAUGAAUUUGGCCUACUUUUCUGAGCACCCUCCUGGGAAUUCCAGCCCUCAGGUUAGAAAAGAAGAGGAGAUGAUGAGGUAGAAGGCUUUGCUUCUUUCGGAUGUCAUGAGAGGCUGAGAUGCUCAGGCCAUGGCUGUGCCUUCCAGGGCACCCCCGUGCUAACCCAGGUGCUGACUCCUCCUCCGCUUCCUCUGGCAGUGCCCAUGACCUCAGCACGUAGACCCAACGCGGGGAGCCGUGCUUUUCGCUGGUCACCGAGUGGCUGCUGUGCUGUGGCUUCCCUGGCUAGGGCAAGGACGUCAGGUCUGCCCAUCUCUCAGUGGCCUGCCACUCAUUCAGCUCCCCUGAGGGCUUCCUCCUGUGACAGUGUCCUCGGAGGCCAGCAGCCCUCCUGCAGCCCGUGGACGGCGAUGGGAUUGGUGGAACGCAGUUCCCUCCGUGGAUAGAGGGUGAAGAUGUCACAGGCACAAGUUUAGGUGCUGGGUGUGGGCAUGUGUGACAGCGUGGUUGUGAGCAUGUGGGUGAUGGGGGUGUAACCACCUCUAGGGACCAGUGUCCUUCAUAGUCUGCCUUUGAACAAUGGCAGUGACUACUGAUCAGCUUCUUAGGACUUCGGCACUCACUCUGUAGGAGAUCACGCCUUCCAAACUUCCCCUUUUACGGUCUGGCGGCCUUGCAGUAGACACGACUCAGAUGUAAACCUGCUUCUGUGUCUCAGAUGUCUGUCUGCCUCUUCAGCAUCAUGGCUGAGAACUGUGGCUGUUGUAGUGUCAGGUGACCCACAGACCAGGAAGAGGGGAAAACGGUUCUUAGCGGGGCCUGGACAACUGCAUUUGCGUGGGGAGAGAAGAUGUACGACGAGGCAGAGAGGCGAAGCCUGUCUUGAUUUGCUGGUGGGCUGCCGUGGGCUCCCUGGUGCUGAGCGGGGUCCUGUGCUGGAUUGUUGGGGUGGCUCUGGGCCCAGCAUCUGGGAGUGGCCCUGCCUGCUGCCAGUCUGCCUCUAAGCAGCUUCCCUGGAGAGACUGGGGGUAGGACAGGCCUUUUGAGAUCCUACUUUCUUAGCAGGAAGGACGCCUUUUUCCCAGCAGGCUGGCGGGGUCUGUGCCCUCCUUUGAGGUGCUUAGUCCCACAACCAUGCGCUUGGGGGAAGACUGAAGCCGGGUGGAUUGAGCCGAGUAUUUCUUGUUAUUUUUCCAUGCUCUCUGUCUUUAUUUUUGAUUUGUGAUCUAAAAUAUUUGGGGUUGAACUGAUUUAAUUUAUUCCUCUGCCCUUUUUGUGCUGAGGAAACUGGGGUAAGGUUCAAAUGUGAAAUUUUCUGAUUUUAUUUGGGGUGGGGGACAAGGUUGACGAAACAGUAGCUUCUAGGGAGAAACAGAUUUCACGGAGCCUCCAGCAUCUUUGGCACUGCCCACGAUCUGAAUCUCCAGGGCUGAAGACUGCGUGGCUGGAAUCUGUUUCUUCCUAUUUUGUUAGCAAAAGCCUUUUCCAGGCUUGGGGGUGGGGUGGGGGAAGAAUUGUACAUAAAGUACAUUUUAUUAAUCUGUAGAGAAACCUAGGAAAAGAAAAGCUAAUGGUUAAUCUUGGGCUUGCUUUGCUUGCAUGUAAAGGAGCUUUGGGGGCACUGCAGGGAUGGCUGGGGAGCUGCAGGAAGGGGCAGAGGGUGGAGCUGAGCGGGUCAUGGAAGGCUCUGUUGAGUCCAGCCUCUGUGGUACUCUAGGAGCUGUGCACAUUCCCACCGGGGCUUCUAACCCAGCCCUGCCUGGGUAUCUUCUUCAUAUAAAGUGGAUCUAGUAGGCAGUGUGUAGAGCCCCAUGUGGCUGUGUGUGUUGCUUUAGGGAGAGGGCCAAAGAGGUGCCUUAUUGGCCAGCUCUAGAUUGACUAGGGUAAUGGAUGGGGCACUGGUGUUUCAGGAGGGGGAGUUGGAGAACUGGAGGGUGGAGGGGAGGCCUGUGUGCUUUGCCAGGUGUUGGUGAGGCUGGAAGGGGCACAGAGGGUGAGGUCAGGCAUGGGUUAGGAUGGUGAGACCACCCCAGGGGACACCAAGCCUCAGCAUCUCUUUGAGUCAUGUGAUAACUUAGUUACUUGUAAGGGUGCAGGGUACACACUGGGGGAUCAUCCCAAGAUGACGAAGAAUGAUUGCCUGGUGGGCAUCUGGCUGGGGAGUGGUAGCCAUGCAGGGCAUGUGGGAGGGGGAUCUGGGCAUCAGGGACGGAUUGUGGGGUGGGGUCCUGCAUGUGAACGCAGACUGGAUCUUGGGAGAGGUCUUGCUUCUUAGCUAGAUCUUCCUUGCUUCUUCUAGAAUUAGCCUCUAACACUAAGUGCCCAAACCAAACAUGGACAUCUUCUUUAUAUUGUAUUUCAACUUCAUUUGUUUUGGGGGCUCCUCAGGCCCAAAGCUGAGAAACUUGUCUUGAGAUGCCCAUCCUAUCACCAGCUCUUCAUCAGUGGAGAAGGAAGUGCCAUUCUCAUUUUCCUAAGCUGCAGCGGUGGGUUGCCUCUCCGUCCACAAUCUGAAAAUGUUCAUGGGCCUUGGUGAUGGUGAUGGUGAUAGAGAGGGGGAGCUGGAGCCUGACGUGCCUUCAUCCCCCUUUCCUCUUGAGGUAGAGAGGCUUCCUUCCGGCCAUGAAGUUGCACAGUGGCUUCGUGAGGCCUUCUCUUUACUUUCUCUUCUUUUGAUAGGCUAAAGUCACUAGUCUGUGGUGGAGGUGGGAGGGCAAAAGAGUUUCACCUGAAACUCUUGGCUUGACCAGCCAUUCUUCUCUCUUUAAUGUCUCCAGCUCUGCUUCUUUUUAGAUUAAGAGGCAGAAUGAAAAAUCUCUUCUUUAGAAGAAGUCAGUAAACCAAGGAUCAAAGCCCAGAUUGGACUUUCGCACUCUUACCAGCUUGCUGUUUGGCUAGGGGUACCAAUCACCACCCUUCCCUCUGACUGCGAGUGAAUCCACACUGGUUCAGAGCCUUAUUUCUGGGUUCCUGUCUGUACUCUCAAAACCUUCUUUCAGGAGCAAGUAUAAUAACCCCACCAGAUGUUCUGUGUGUUGGGUUGCCGAGAAGGUGGAAGUUUUUUUCAACCUCAUUUUAAGCUGUUAGAAAAACACUCAGUAGAUUGAAUUUGGUCCAAAGACACCACCAUCCCCUGAGGGAUCCCAUGUAGGAUAAGGAUAAAUGAAGCAUCCAUACAGGGGUCAUUAAUGGCUGCUCACAUCUUAGAGAAGGAAGAGUCUGGGUAUCUUGGUUGCCAUAUACUCUGGUGGAACAGUGGCCAGUCAUUAAAAUCACAUGGGUGUUGUCUUCUGCGGUGUAGAAGACAGUAGUAGUAGUUAGGGUUUCGGACGAGAGCUGGUGAAAAGCUACCGGCUUUGGAGCCCUGGCUGGGAGAGCUAGAUUGGACAGUUUUAACCCCGUGGCUCAAAUGCUCAGCUCCUGUCACUGGUCCUUGGUUGUCACCAUUCCCAUCACACUAGAUGGGGACGUGAAUGGCUGCCUGGGCCUGCCUUUCUUUCGGGUCUUGAAGAAGUGUGCUCCACCAAUCCUACCUCUCUGUGGCACUGGAUUUCCUGGAUUUAUUUUGCGAACUAGGGCAGGUUCUCCCUCGCCACCCCGUAUACACACCAGUUAGCUUCCCUUCCCUUUUCCUUUCCCCACUUCUGUAUGGCUCCAGGGAUCGUGAACAUGUGCGUGGUUUACGAUGGGGAGGUGGUGGGAGGGGCAGGGAAUCUCGGAGGGCAGGGGGUUGGGCUGGGGAGGUGACUUGCAUUUUCGGCCUUAGAAAUGCUGCGGGCAUGCACGUGUGGGGUUUUCAUAUAAGCCAUGGGAGGGGCGAGUGCCCAGCCCUCCUCACGCUGGUGGUAGAACCCAGGGCUUUGGCCUCCUUUUGGCAUAGUGGUCUAUGAAGCUGUAUUUCUGGUGGAGGGAUGAGCCUCCUCACGGUCAUCUUGCAGUUCUUGAAAGGGUAGUUGUCAGCCACUCUAUCAAUGAGGUUUUAUAUGGCCUCCCAUGAACAACGAGAGGUGUGCCAUGGCCGACGGUGUCCUGGCAGGGCUGGAGAAGGGAUUGUCUCAUGUGUCCUUCUGCAGGCACCAGGUUGUCCCCCUGGUCUCUAACCCCCAGCCAGCUGUCUAGUCCAGUGUUUCUUUUCUGGAUUCAGGAAGUAAGUGGGGUGUGUGUGUGUGUGUGUGGGGUGUGUGUGUGUAUGUGGUGUGUGUGGUAUAUGUGUGUGGUGUGCAUGUCUGUGUGUGGUGUGCAUGUCUGGUGUGUGUGUGUGUUGUGUGUGGUGUGUGUAUCUGUGUGUGGUGUGUCUGGGUGGUGUGUGUGGUGUGGUGUGUGUAUUGUGUGUGGUAUGUGUUGUGCGUAUUGUGUGGUGUGUUGUGUGUGGUGUGUCUAUUGUGUGGUUGUGUAUGUGUGUGGGGUGUGUGUGGUAUGGUGUGUGUGUAUCUGUGGUGUGCGUGUAUGUGUGAUGUGUCUGGUGUGUGUGUGUGUGAUGCAGUGUGUGUGGUGUGUUGAGUGUGGUUUGGUGUGUGUAUGUUGCGUGUGGUGUAUGCUUGUGGUGUGUCUGGUGUGUUUGGUGUGUGUGUGUUUGGUGUGUGUGGUGUGUCUGGUGUGUUUGGUGUGGUACAUGGACUGUGUGUGGUGUGUGUGUGUGCUAUGUGUUUUGUGUAUUGUAUGUGGUGUGUUAUUGUGUGUGGUAUGUGUGUAUUGUGUGUGGGUGUGGUGUGUGGUAUGGUGUGUGUAUGUCUGGUGUGUGUGUGUGUGUGAUGUGUCUGGUGUGCAUGUGUGUGAUGCGGUGUGCAUGUGUGUGAUGUGUGUGUGUGUUGUGUGGUUUGGUGUGUGUUGUGUGUGGUGUGUUGUGUGUGUGUUGUGUGUGUGUGUGGUGCGUGUGUGGUGCGUGUGUGGUGCGUGUGUGGUGUGUGUGUGUUUGUGUGUGUGGUGUGGUGUGUCUGUUGUGUGUGGUGUGUGUGAGAGAGAUUUGUACAGACAUGCUGAUUUGCCUGCGUAGUGUCAGGCCCAGGAGACCCUCCUUUGUUUGGCUCUUUUGCUAGACAACUUCUGUUUGGGUAGGAGGGUCAAAUUAGUAAUGCACCAUCUUUAAUGUAUUUUUUAUGGAGACUGUACAUAAAAUUAUAUAAAUCUACAGAAUUGGUUCUAUUUUAAGGAGAGAGGGGAAUGUAUGUGGGAGGCAAGGAUCAGAUGCAAUCGUGGAGACUGGGAGCUUCGGGCGAGUGGCACUCGGGUGUGGGGAGCGGGAGGGCAAGAGAUGAGUGCCGGGCAAGAUGGGCAGGGGCCCGUGCCCUCUGCACACAUAUAUAAAUAUAAAGAACACCUAGAUAAAGUCUAUAUAUCUCUAUAUCUAUAUGAAGUCAUAGUUUGCUUUAUUUUUGUACCUGUGCUUAGAGAUGUUUUGAGCAGUGCUACCUUCCCAGGCAGUCUGGGAUACUAGCUCAUGCCUUGACGCCACCUCCUUCCCUGCUCUUCCUUUGGUAUUCUCUCUGUUCAGAGUUGCUUGGGUCUUUCUGAUGGAAAUGUGUAUAUAUGAAAAGUUUGUAAAAUAACAAAACAAAUAACCCACCUGCAGGAAGGACAAGUGAGCUGAAGGUUGUGUGGAGCUGCAGGAUCUGAUAGCCCUAAAGAACCAGGACCAAUGUGUCUCUUGCCACUUGGGAGGGAUGUUGACUUGAACUUCUUUGCAGAGGGGCUUAACAGGGCAAGGCUGAGGAGAUGAAAACUGUGACUCCAUCCCCACGUGGCUGUGGAAAGGUAACCAGUUCCUCAGAGAAAACCUGGCUUCACAGCAUUAGAAAGGGGGUGGUUGAGACUACCUAGGGACCUACGGUGACACCUGUCUUGGUUUGUAGCACUGUAGCUCAGACAGCUCAGACCGCUCAUAGAGGGCAUGGCAAUGGGAGAGUUUGUGAGGCUGGCUGCCUGGGCUUGGUCUUGGAGAACACAUGGCCUGUUUAGUGUUGCUGCAGAUUCUUAGAGCCAGUGUGAAUGUGGUAUGUAGUAUAAAUAUGUCAUCUAUGUUUUUUUCAGUUAUUUUUAAUUGGAAAUAAAGUGCCAUUGCAAAUAGGAUGCUCCAAUCCUGGGACACUGAGUGGAGGAUGAGGAGGGAGAGAUGAACUGUGGGCCGGCCUGGGAGAGGGGGUCUUAGUGGAACCUUCCUUCUGGCCUCCAGCCGGGGACUUACAAAACUGAACAAUGUAUUGGCAGAACUGGACCCACAAUGGGAGAUUCUGGGGAGCAGGAGUUCACUUGUAUCUGAGCAGGAAGCAGUGUGCCCUGAAGAAUACCUCUCUGAGCAAAUUCCAGACCUCACACAUAUGCAAGGGCUCUGCCUUGCAGCCUCAGCAAGCGUCUCCUGGUGCUAGCUCCUUCCUGACUUGCCCGGAGCUCGGAGUGAUGUAUUUGAAGCUGGUGCUGGGCCAGAUGGUGCAGGCAGUGAGGAGAGACUCAGGACUGCAACCUUUCGGCUCCUUAUUCCUGCUCAUCACUCAGAAAAGGGCAGUACUAACCCCUUUCCUAACCAAGACAUGGCACUCCCUAAGAGCUCUUGUCUAUAGAGUUUGGUCCUUAGAGGAAAGCAGAUACCUUCAGCGUGAGAAGGGCUUGGUUGACAGUUUUGGGGUAUUAUGGGAAGAGUAGGUUGGGGUAAAGCUUGAGUCUAACUCUUGAUCCUUACAUGGACCUAUGAGGCCCUGCCAUUCAGUCAGGCACUGUCCUUGGGUCCUCAAAUUAACUGCUGAGAACACUCCCCACUUUCCGAGGACGCUGAUGGGAAAUGGGCUCUGUCCAUGCAGCUGGAAGGAUCCAGUGCUGGUGCCACUGUCAGUGGCACCAUCCUUGCCUUGAAUGAUCUUUCUUGCAGGCUCCUGCAGCUGAGUGUUUCUUGUAAGAUUUUUCAGGGGGAUUGGGCAAGAAGAAGAGGUGCAAAUUCUGUUCCCUUCCUACCUUGAAGCCUUCCCAGACCACCACGGUCUCUGCACAAGGGAGGCUCCCAUUACUGUUCUGUUGGCUUCUAGACCCACCAUCCCCUCUCUUUCUGUGGACUCUGCCCGACUUCUGGCCACAUGCAACCAGCAGAGUAAACUGCUCCAACACCUCGGGCAUGUCCUAGGGCUUGCCCUCCCACCAGGGCCAGCCCAAGAUUAGGUCCUCAGCAGCAUCAAGGUCUGGGAGAGCCACUGGCCCACAUGUCACCAUUCUAUUCCUCAGCCUCCAACAGGACUCUUCAUUUUGGGGAGGGAAAGGGAAGAUGGGGCCAUAGCCCCUACCUUGAAAUUGUACAGUGUGGAGGGGAUGUUAGUGCCUACCUGUGACCUUUCUGCUCCACUGCUCAGCAAGAUGAGGUAAGGUUGGGUGUCAGAGGGGACCUCCAGCUUCUCUGAAGAGCCAGCCCUUAAGGCACUUGGAGCAAAGGUCAUUGAGAUCAGCUUUAUGUGGAGUAAGGAGGAGGCCUGGGAACCGCUUGUGGCAUCAGUUGGGGCGACAGGUGGAUGAGUGUGCUCUGAUGGAGCUUUUACGGCCCACAGCCACUGCCAGGAGCCUGAGCUCUUCCCCAUGCUUGGGACACGUUCCUUGGUCCCCACAGCAGAAUGGACAUUGAAUUUUGGUGCUUUUCCCUUUGGUAGAAGGUGGAGGUAUCUGAGGAGUUGUUUCUGUCUUGCUACCUCUGUCUACUAUAUAGAGCAAGAGUCGGGAAUAGGGAGAUGUGUGAGAAUCACUCUCCCAUGGAUCAGUGUGGGCCCUGUCCCUCUUCCCCACUGUCACCAACCAGCAGCUUGGGGAAAAGGCUCUGUCGUGGAUUUUUGCUGCCUGCUUCCCGCUUCCACUCUUCUUGGCGGUAGAUGUUCAUGGUGAUCCACUUUGGGCGGUCUGAAAGUAGGAGGUGGGGGAAGAGGCAAGCCUGCACACACACUUCCUGUCCACAGGGGGUUGCCUGUGGCAUUGGAGGGUGGAGUCUCAGAGUCCAGGGACUGGGAGGAAGGUACUUGAUGGGAUGGUCUUGAUUCUGGAACUUUAGACUGAGGUGUUAGAAAGGGGAAUUGUUGGCUAGGGGAGAAGAGCAGUUUAACGCUCCACUUGCUAAGUCGUCUGUAUCAGUGUCAGAAGGUCUUGACCUCCCAUUCAGAUUUAAUUUCCUAACUGCCAGGUGUGGGGCUGGGGAUAGAGGGCCCAGAAGGGGGCGCAGUCACUGACGUGAAGGGACCACAUCCCGCUUCAUGUCAGUGACUCCUGCCCCUUGGUCUUCAGUGUUUUUCUCUUCCCCAGGAGGGACUUUGAUCAUGCAGGAUAGAAUUCUCCCAUCGCACACCUGGGGGCAAGUUUUAGAUGAGCUUCUUUCCUCCAUUUCACCUGGUGGUCUGAGGACACACAGAGGGUGGGGGUGAGCAGGCAGUGUGGGUGGGGAGGGGCUACCUCCCCCAGACCCCUUACAAACUCUGUACCUCUCGGUGCGCGGCAGCCUCUUGCUGUAGUUCUUCUUUUCUGGAUAUGACUGUCAGUUUCGUCAUGAGAUUUCUUGCUCUCAUUUCGAACUCUUUCUUUCUUCCACUUUCUUUGGGGGCGACCCCCGAUCCAUGCCAGGUCUUCCUGUGAAGACCGUUCCAACCUCGUUUCCAUUUCUUGAAUGUUGAGUAUUACAACAUCACUGCGCUAGGGUGCUUCAUGGUGCUGUUCUCGAAGAGGCCAGUUGGGCUGAAUCUCCUUCCUCCCACUGGCUCCUGAUAUCUUGCUGUAUUUUGUCUUCUUUCUGAUUUUUCCCUAGGGGUUUGGGGUGGGUGACUUAGGGGCGGCUUUUGUGUUCUCCCUCUCUCUCUCUUUCUUUUCUGUAUGUAUGUAUGGACUGGUUAAAGUGAGUUUGGGCAGCUGACUUUAUGGUAUGGGUUGGCUGACUUUUGUUCAACAUUAAAGACAAACCAACAAAUUGUACAGCUGCACACAGAACACCUUUGAGUGUGAACUUGAAUGGCAACUAGAGGCUUACUUUUUGAACUUCAGGUAUGUAACUCAAAAGUAAAUAAAACCACUAUUUUUUCAGUAAGCUUUUUUUUCUUCUAAAAGAUGACUUAGAAAUCAAACUAUAAGAACAUGAAAUCGGUGCUGUACCAAAGCCUUAUAUGAACAUAUUCUACACUCUGUAUAACCUGUCUGUGAGGAGCUCCCUGCUCUAUCACCCUCUUCUCAAAAGCCUGGGAAUGCCAGCGCGUGCCAAGCCUGGGGCUGGGUCUUGGGGACCUGUGGGCCAAGGGCACCCUGGGAAGUAAAAGAUGACGGUGAGGAUGGGACACCCUUCUGCUGCCUGAGCAGACUGCAAGGAAACCAGAUGUGUGUGUGUGCGCGCACCUGCAUAUAUAUGUGUGCAUACCUGUGCGUGUGUGUGCGUGUGCGUGUGUGCACGCAAGAGAGUGAGAGCGGGAGAGAGCUCACAGGUGCACAGUGUCAUGGUGAAUGUACUAAGUACGAGCUUGAAGGGAGGCCCAGGUUGGCUCUGGGAGUGGGGCGGUGUGGGAAUGAAGGGGGGAUGCUCUCUCCCCUGUUUUCUGCCUCCUUCCCUUCUCCGUCAGGGAAGGGAGGUGUAUUGGAAACAGCUACACUCUCAAUCAGGUGCUUUUUUUCCCUCAAAAUCUCCAAACUCAAAGCAUUUAUAAGGGGCCCUUCCAAUGGGCAGGCACCCCCAGCCACCAAAUCACAGACUUCCAAGAGUAGGAGGAACUGUCUCCUCCCGAACCCUUCCUUGCUUUCCUGGGGAAGAGGGUUCUUCCUGCAGGGACCCUGGGCAUCCUGCUGCUGGGCCUGGGCCUAUAGACUGCCCUGCCCCUUCUUCCCAAACACUGAGAAGACCCCGCUGGAGAUGACCCCAAAGCCACGCCUGCUCUACGGCCCUAAGCAAUAGACGCCUGCCCUGGCUGCUGAUGAUGGUGAUCCCUUUGUCCUUUGACUUGGCAGUCAAAAAUGGAGUGACACCCCAGACUCAGUCAGGAAGAGAACCUGCAGCCUGCCUCAGCUCAGGCUACCACGCCAGGCUCCACUCGCUGGUAUUUCCAGGCUUGCUAAGUACUAACCAACUCAUCCCCAGUAACACUGCAUGUUCAUAUCCUGAAUUACAAAUCAAAAUGAGCAAACACGUGCAUAAGCAAAUGAGAAAAAAGAAGGCACACAUCAAAUGAUGAGAUGUGCAGCCAGUGCAGGUACCCCGGGAGUGUUGCAAGUUAAACUGAUGAAAAGACGUUUAGUAUUUAAUUGCUCCUCAUGUAACAUUACUCUGCUUCAGAAAUGUUUUGUAUUUUGAUAUAAAUAAACAUUUGCUAAAAAA